AUCUGUCUCUUCCCUUGGCUGAGGGUGGCUGUGCUAUUGGAAUCCAGGCCCUUAUUCAAGCGUAGCCUCUGGAUCCAGGUUUUGGAAUGAUCCUGGAGAUUUCAAGAGGCCCCCUGCCCUCCCUGCCCGCUGACCCGUCUCUGUGUGCACUGCUCUGGGCCAGAGUCUGGAGACCAGCUGGGCCAGCUCAGCUCACCUCCCUGCUGCUCCUUGUUGAGACCCCAUCACCCAGUUCCAGCCCAGCCCCCUCUCAGCCCUGGACUCUCUCUUUGCCCUGUCCCCGACUUUAAUAAUGGGACACUCCUCGAUAUCAGGUGAUUCAGGCACUGGGGGAAAGGCUGGUGAACUGCCUGUGGAAAACCAGUUCCUAAGCUGGAAGAAGCAGAGAGAAAAUCGUGACCCUUGAUCUGCUCCACCAUCUGCCACCAGGGCCUUUUGAGGAGGUCGUCUUCUCAUCUUUCUGCCUCAGGCCUACUUUUCAACAACUCCCCAGCAGGAGAGUCUGUGGUCUCCUUUGGGGUCUUGCUGUUCUCCUUGUACCAGCAGCUCCAGAGUUUGUUGUGGGUCUCAUUGUAACCUGUACUGAUAUAGAUGGGCGCUCUUGUUAGUGGAUUUCAGUCUCAUCCUGGGUUCCAGUCUCUUGUUCUUUGAGGGAGGGGCCUCAGAGGUAGGCUAGUGCUGCUGGUGGUGACUUCCUGAGGAAUGGGAUCUUCCCCUCUCCCUCUACAGAGCUGCACACUGUGAUGGAGACUCCUCUGGAGAAGGCCCUGACCACUAUGGUGACCACGUUUCACAAAUAUUCGGGGAGAGAGGGUAGCAAACUGACCCUGAGUAGGAAGGAACUCAAGGAGCUGAUCAAGAAAGAGCUGUGUCUUGGGGAGAUGAAGGAGAGCAGCAUCGAUGACUUGAUGAAGAGCCUGGACAAGAACAGCGACCAGGAGAUCGACUUCAAGGAGUACUCGGUGUUCCUGACCAUGCUGUGCAUGGCCUACAACGACUUCUUUCUAGAGGACAACAAGUGACCAGGGCUGCCCUCCACCCUCACCCUCCACCCUUUGCUGCUGACCUCGGCUGCUCCUCUCACAGACCCUCUUUGGCCCCCUGCCCUCCUCUCCCUCCCAGAUGGACCCUUCCAUGGGAGGAAAUAAAGUUUCCAUCGCAGGUGCUGGGA